AAUGUAGCAAGAAGCAGAAACACUGGACAGUCUCUUACAGUUUGAUCUGAUAUGAUGACAAUAAAGGUAAUUUAUGAAACAAUUUUUUUUAAGCUUUAGGACUUAAGAACAAUUGUUGUGUCUCAGCCGUGGCAGUUCUGUCCUAUACGUCUGGCCUAAACUGUCUUUUCACAGCUUCCUAGCUGGGGGAGGUGAUUGUCAAAUUAUAAUUGGGUGAGAGGAUGUAAACUGUAAAUUGUGCAGUUUGCAAGUAGAAAUUAGGGUGGCUCCACAUAUAUAAGCUAAAAUAAAUAAUAUAGAACUAAACUGUUAGUAAUUUAUCAACCCAUUGCCAUCUUGAGAAUCAUAAUGUGUAUUUGUGAAACAACAGAAUGAUUUGCAGGCAGCAGAUGUAAUGCUUAUGCAGAGUUGCUGGGAAACUGCUUUAUUCACACAAGGAACUGAGGGACAUUAGAGACGAGCUGUCACCUGAGAGUAUCAGUCAGCUCUUGGAGUUUUCAGUAAGAUUUCUUUCCCCUUAUACAGCGAAUACUGUUCUCCUUUCCUCCCCGUCGAUUGGUUUCUCGGCAUCUACUUGGUAUGACACAGUAAACAGGCUCUAUUCUCUGUUUUCAGCAACAUAGAAAUAUUGUUCAGCCUGUCCUGAUGGAGUACAGCAACCUGCUGAUUAAGGGAUUAACAAUUUUAAAAGUAUUUUGUACAGUGGUUCAGGGAAGAUUAGAGAGGGUUGAGUAUAAUUGUGGUUUGGAUGCUUUGCUUUUGCCAAAAUUGGCAGUUGUUUCAACCAUUCUUAAUAUUUUCAUCUAAAAUUGCACAGUAAUUAAACCCUGCUAAACACUUUUAAGUAUUUGCAUAGAGGUGAGAUAAUGUUCUAUUGAUUCUUUUAAUUUGUAAGAGUAGAUUAAGUUUAUCUUUAUAGUUGCAGUAAUAAAAUGAAUUAUACAAAUAUAUACAGAAUUCCAGGUUCUUUGUGUAUAAUGCUACAGAAAAACUGGUUGGUUUGUUUUUUUUCCAUGCGUCAGUAGUAGUAACCCUUAUCUUUGAACUUGAGGUAAUUUUGUCAGUUGGUAAUACAUUGAAUUCUUAGGGUAGCAUCAGAUUUUGGUUUAUGAGCCAUUUAAGAAUAUUGAUUAGAAAAGAUUUGAUUUUCUUCUUAGAGGCAUAUGAUUAACAUAAAAAUACCUUGUUAAUGUUGUGACCACAGUGUGUGUUUGUGAUAAAUUAAAAGAAUAGGGGCCUGGCACAGUGGCUCACUCCUGUAAUCCUAGCACUUUGGAAGGCAGAGACGGGCAGAUCACGAGGUCAAGAGGUUGAGACAAGCCUGACCAACAUGGUGAAACCCCAUCUCUACUAAAAAUGCAAAAAUUAGCUGGGCGUGGUGGCGCAUGCCUGCAAUUCCAGCUACUCAGGAGGCUGAAGCAGGAGAAUCGCAUGAACCCGGAAGGUGGAGGUUGCAGUGAGUUGAGAUCGCACCACUGCACUCCAGCCUGGGUGACAGAGCAAGACUCUGUCUCAACAACAACAACAACAACAAAGAAUAGGUUAAAAUUUAAAGAAGUCUUAGGCUUUUGACUUUGUGUUACUAUAAUUUCAUGUAUAGAGUGAAUAUAAAAUGUUUAAGGUUUCUUGGUUUUAGUUGGAAGAUUGGAGAGAAUAUAUCAGGCAUUGAACUUUGAAUGCUUAAAUUAGUAGAAUAAUUUUUUAAUUGAACAUUUUACUUAACUAGUCCUGCUCAGCAAAUCCUGUGUUAUAUGUUGCUAUCUUCAAAUGUUGGAUAGAGAAAUUACUUAAAAUAUAUAUUUUAUUUAGAUAUGUAAUUAGACUGCUACUUGUCUUUUCAGUUACUGUUUAAUCAGAAAAUGUAAUCAUCUCAAUUCAAAUGAAAAUCUCUAACAUAUGGCAUAGAUGCUGUGGGUGUUAUGGAAUCUAUAAGAAGAAUCAAUGCUGUUGGUAUAUUAAAUGUAUUUCCUCUAAAAAUAAUUUUGGAAGUUACAAACACUCCUACAGAUUUAACACUUUUGUUGCUCUGUGACUAAUGAGGAAAUAAAAUUUUUUAAAAAAUUUAAGUAGUUAGGGUUUUAAAGCUGUUUUAAAUUUUGCCUGAGAUAACUCAUAUCCUAUUUGUGAAUUACUUAGAGGACUUUUAAUUAAAGUAACUCAAACCAACUUGGUUAGCUAAGAAAGAUCCUAGUCAUUGCCUGUGAUAGAUUCUUUAUGCUCAUAAUGGUAACAAACUAAUAUUUUUUGAUUUAGGGGUUUUCCUAAACUAUGGUGCCUUACUUUGUUUAAGCAGACACUGUCCUUUGUCAGUGAUUUUUUUUUUUUUAAAGCUUAGCUAAAAAUCUGCAGAAAGCCCCAAACCUAUCUUUUUUCCCCCCAUAUUCAGCUUUUCAUUUUGGACAAUAGGCUAGUAGAAUUUUAAACUGUGACCUUAGUAUUACUAAUGCAUAUUAAGGUCACAGUAAGUAUACCGAAGGAAAUGAUUGAUUUUUAAAGCAGCUUUAUUGAGAUAUAAUUUGCAUACCAUAAAAUUUACCUGUUUUGGCCGGGUGCAGUGGCUCAUGCCUGUAAUCCCAGCACUUUGGGCGGUCGAGGCGGGUGGAUCACAAGGUCAGGAAACAGAGACCAUCCUGGCUAACACAGUGAAACCCCGUCUCUACUAAAAAUACAAAAAAUUAGCCGGGUAUGGUGGCGGGCGCCCACUACUCAGCUACUCAGGAGGCUGAGGCAGGAGAAUGGCGUGAGCUCAGGAGGCGGAGCUUGCAGUGAGCUGAGAUUGCGCCACUGCACUCCAGCCUGGGCGACAGAGCAAGACUCCGUCUCAAAAAAAAAAAAAAAAAAAAAAAUUUACCUGUUUUAACGGUAUGAGGAAACUUGAUUUUUACAUUAAACAAAAUCCCUGGGAAAUCACCUGGACAGAUACUUUUAACAAAUGUGAAUUUUCAGAUGCUCCAUCUUUUCUUCUCCCUAGAUUUUGGUUCAUUAGGACUCAAACUUUAGUAAGUAUUAGGAGACUUGUGAAAACGAAAGACUCUGAAAUCCCAGUUCUUUUUAACUUUUUAAUUGUAAGGAAGAUACAUUUAUUUCUGGAUUUUAUAUAUAUGUAUAUAUAUAUUAUAUUUAAGUUUAAAAACCUGAAAGCUUCCAGUAUCAGAUUACUGUAGUGACAAGCAUUUUAAUAUGUGCAGGAAAGAGUAAAAAGUAAAGACUUUUCUGCAUGCUGAAGUUACAGUACAGCAGAGGAUUCUCACCUUAGUUUUACAAAAUAAAAAGGGGCCUUAGCUUCAAAACUGGAUUUUGCUUGGGGAUGGAUUUGCUGCUAGAAUUUUGUGAAAGAUUAUGUAAAAAUAUUUCCAUUAUUUUCCUUGUCAGUUUUGGGACACUUGUGCCGGAGUGCUUUGUUAUUGUAAGCUGAAACUUCAGUGCACAGUGCACUGUGGGUGGAAAAGCUUUAAGACAUUCUAGACCCUAAGCAGCAAUGGCCAUUUUGCUGUGAGUUUGUAAAGUAAAAACGUUCUCUCCCCCUUUUCCUAAGAUGUGCAUGUAGCAAGGAUGGCAAAGUCCUCCCUGUAGCUCUUGCUUGUGGUCUUGGUAUGCAGGGAGUUUACCAGGAACUUCUUAUGUAGACCCUCUAACAGCAUAAAAGGCUUCUUUUUUCUUUCUCACAUGUUCUUGUAUUCUUAGGGACAUUUUUUAGCUCAGAGUAACCUAUGAUAGGAAAAGAAGAUAACUUCUAGAAGUGGUAAGUUUUGUAAUAUGACAGAUUCUCAAGCAGGAUGUCGCUUCCCCAUUCUGUACCAUCUGACUUAAGUUUUGUACGUCUGGAGAGCAGUGGCAGUAAUUGUAUAAUUUUUUGGCAGCUGCACAAUGUUUUGACGACGUUGCUUUAGUCUCCAAAGUAGACAGUUCAGAUUUUUUUUUUUUUUCAAAAAGAACUUUCUCAGAAAGGCAGUAUAGUGUAUAGUGUUGAGAGUACAGGCUUAGAGGCCCUUAACGAGAUCCAUGCUCCAUGCUUCUCGUUGUAUGGUCUUGGGGAUAUUAUUGUCUUUCUGAUUCUCUAUUUGUAAAGUGUAAAUAACAAUACCUACCUCAUAGGGUCAUUCUGAGGAUUAAAUAAGACCAAACCUAGAAUUUAGUGGACACUCAAAUAUUUGGUAAAUACAUUUUGAAAGAAUCAGACUAGUAGAUGAGGGAUAGAUAGGAGCAGGGAAUUCUUGGAGUAGAUUGGAUCUUGUUGCCAUUUGGUUAAGUCUUCUGAUUUUCCAUUGUAUUUGCACAAUAUCCAUGAAGCCAGAUUUUGUGCUUUUGAAAAACACUUGGAUUAGAAUUUGGUGUAUUAGUUUGCUGAGCUGUUGUAACAAAGUGCAACCAACUGGAUGAUUUCUACAACAGAUAUUUAUUGUCUCACUAUUCUGGAGGGUAGACCUCUGAAAUCAAGGUGUUGGCAGGGUGGGUUCUUUGUGAGGGCUGUGAAGGAAGGAUCUGUUCCAGGCAUCUCCCUGGCUUUUAUAUAGCCAUCUAUCUGGAGUUCUGACUGUAUGUGUGUCUGUCUCUAAAUUUUUCCUUUUUAUAAGAAUACUAGUCGUAUUGGAUUAGGACCUACCCCAAUGGCCCUAUCCUAACUUGAUUACUACUGCAAAGACCCCCCUCUCUCUAGAUAUGGUCACUUUCUGAGGCACUGGAAAUUAUGACUUUAACAUAUGAAUUUUGAAGGGACACAAUUUAAUCCAUAACAGAGGUAUAUCAGACAUGAGAAUGAAACAGACUUUUACUUACAACAUUUUCAUUUUUUUAAUUGUGCGUAUUUAUUAAACUUUGAUGUAAAUUAAUGGUAUAAUCUUUUUUUCUUUUACUGAGCCCAGACAUUCAUUUACCUAAACUUAAGUGAAGUGUAUGUGGCACUUGAAAAAGAUUGGUAAAAUUGAACAAAAAUUCCUUAUUUCCUUGUCUUAGUUAUUUUGUAUGUUACUAUUGAGAUGAGGGAGGAAUGUUUGAGUUUGAGUGACUGAAAUAUCAAGGGAGGAGUUAAAUUCUCUGGAGGCUGACCUGAAGUCAUUUUGGCAUUUAAACUGGUUUCAGAAUGGUACAUAUCUACUAAAUAUAGAAUUUACUGGUGUACAUGUUGUACGAAAUCUUAUGUGUAUUAGUUUUCUAGGGCUACCGUAACAAGGUAGCACAAACUGGGUGGCUUAAGACAACAGAAUAUUUUUCUCUCACAGUUCUGGAGUCCAGAAAUUCAAAACCAAGGUUUGGGCAGGAUCAUGCUUCUGAAGGCUCUAGGGAAGAAUACUUCUUUGCCUCUUUUAGCUUCUGGUAUUUACUGUAGUCCUUGGAGUUCCUUGGCUUGUGGCAAAAUAAUUCCAAUCUCUUCCGCUGUCUUCAUGCAGCCUUCUUGUGUGUAUCCAUAUCUUUCUUUUUUCUUAUAAGGAUACCAGUCAUUGAAUUUAGGGCUUACCCUAAUCCAGUAUGACCUCAUCUUGAUUAUAUCUGCAAAGACCCCAUUUCGAAAUAAAGUCACAAUGGCAGGUAUAGGUUGAAUAUUCCUAACCCGAAAAUCUAAAAUGCCCCCAAAUUUGAAACUUUUGAGCUCCUUUUUGAGCACUCAAAAGAAAUGCUCUUUGGAGCAAUUUGAAUGUCAGAUUUUUUUAUUAGGGAUACUCAACUAGUAUGUAUUCUACAAGUACCCUUAAAUUAAAAAAAAAUUAAAAAUCUGAAACACUUCUGGUCUCAAGCAUUUUUGAUAAGGUUAAUUCAACCUUUACUGGGGUUAGGACUUAAACAUAUUGUUUUGGGGAACAUAAUUCAACCCACAACACUUGUCCAUUGCUUCUUAAAAUCACAUUUACUGUUAAUUUCUCUCUUAAAUUCUCCAGUUAUUCUGACUAGUAAAUGGACAGCCUUGUUUCCACACAUUAAUGUACUUGAGUGUGACAGCUGAGAACUCUCCCACUUUCCUGCAUGUUAACCUAUUGCCUUGGUUUUCCAGCUACAUAAUCAUGCUUUCACUCUUUGUCCUUCUGUUUCAGCAGUUUGUUGGAAAUUCUUAGAUUGGUUUUGGUUUCUUGUUGUCUUUACCAACUCAGUGUCAUAAGUUGUAUUUAAAAUUGUUGAACUUUCUGUUUUAUAACUUACAGUAGAUUUUAUCUCCAGGAACUUUUUUGUAAUUGGAAUGCAUAUUGACUUACUACUGAAUGCUUAUUACUAAUAACACUUUCUAUUGAGACAACAAUGUUCUCCGCAGAAUGAAUGGUAUGAGCACAUGCAUUGGAAUGAAAACAUUUGAGACUUGAUUUGAAAGCUGUAUUCACAGGUUUUGCUGUGAAAAAUGUUAUGCUUUAUUGGGAAGUAAUGCUGAAAAGGUAGAGAUUAUGCAUAGGUUCACCUCCAAGACCGGCCUGUCAAUGAAGCAUAAAUAAAUUGGGGAGAUCGUUAUUUCGGCAAAGUAUUAUGUGGCUUUACUGUUUAAAAUAUGUUGGCAUGUGUGUGUAUAAAGCUAAAAUAAGCCAUUGAUCAUGUAUACUUUUUAAAAUAAGUGAUUUGAGUUUUUGUGGGUAUGCACUGAAGGAACUAUCUUUUAAAUUGUUUAAUUGUGGAUACUAUAUUAUCUUUUCUAUUCUCAAUAUUUGUGACAUAUAAUAAAAUGUUUUGUACUCAUUCUUUCUAAUGUGUUCAUUUUGCUCUGUAUAAACUUCACGGCCUUUAAAAAGGCAUCUGGGAAAAUGUCAGGGUGUUUUUUUUUUUUUUUUUUGACAAAUUGGAAAUGCCACAUUCAGAUGACUUCUUAGGAAGAAUAAAAUGUUGUUAUUCUGAGUCUAGGUUUGAACUUUAAAGAUUCAUCUCAUUUUAGUAUAAAGUGUUUUAUUUACCAAGAACUUCAGUAGGCUUUCUUGUCACCUGAAUGGCAAGUUAAUUCAGAAGGAACGUAUCAAAAUAAUAAAAUGAGAAAAGUUAGGAACCAGCAUUAGCUGAGUCACAAUCCCCUGCUUAACCUUAUUUGCCAGUGCGCACUCAGAAGAACUGCUUCUUACCAAAACAUCUGUCUCUUCAGCUUUCAGUAGGAAGCAGUGUCCUUUGGCUUACAAAGAAGUGGUAACAGAACUAAGCGAAGAUGAAUGAAACAGUUUGAAAUUGGCAUUGGUAGAUUUAGUUUCUUUUUUUAAGCAAUUAAAAGCCCGCAGCACUGUGAUUGGCAUUUUUGACGUUUAGCUUGUGCUACUUAGUAUCAGAGACUUAGUAUCAGGGACUUAUCAGUAAGUCCCUGAUACUUACUGUAAUUGCUGUAUCUUGCUAAGACCUGCUGUUUAGAUAUUUCUUAGGUCAUAAAAUGAAUGCUUAUUAGAUUGUUUCUUGUGAGAACUAAGGACCAAUGUAGAGAUCAUUUAUUACCAGAGUAUGAUUAUUAGCAUUUUAUGCCAAAGGAAUUAUUUCUGCAUACCCCAUUCAGCAUUUUUAUAUACUGAGAAAUAACAUUAAUAAAUAUCUAAUUAUUUGUCCUUGACUCGGCAUUUUUCUUCAUAGUUGUUAAUAUAAUUAAUUUUUUCACCAAGUAAUUUUUUUAUCCUUUGACACGUGAAAAGACUAAUCAUAUAAUUACAGUGUUUUCAUCAUGCUACUGCCCUACUCUAACAUUUUGAGUUGUUUACAGUGCUUACAGAGUCCAGGCUUAACAUCCAUAUAUAUGUACAAGGUUGUCUAAAGUUUUGAGGAGAGACAAGUAUAUAUUGGCAUUAUAUGCUUGUACAGCUACUGCUAACUUAUCUUUCUGAUUCUUCUCUAAGGCCCCAGAGCUAAAUCUGCAGUUCAGCUGGGUUAGUCAUUUUAUUACUCCAGAACAUCCUGUUUCCCUCAGCCUUUCUGGAAUACUCUGUUCCCUCUGUUCAUUUUCUUCCUUUCUUCAAAGGCUAGCUCAAAGCUCAGAUUUCUUGAAAGGAGAAACUUGUCCUAAUCAGUCCAACUCAGAAAAGUCUUUUCAUCUUCUGGUCUGUAAGAAAUAGUCGGUUCUACUCAUUUCGUGUUCAUGCUUGGCUGAGCUCGUCUUUUACAUCUUCUAAGAAGCUUUUCUAGACUUCGAUUUUUCUCAUUUCUCUUAUAUUUUAUUUAUAUUGUUUAUAGGUGGGUCCUUCUAUUCUUUCAAGCAUGUAAGUUCUUGUUAGAUAAUAUUUUCCAUUAAGGUUUUUUUCUUUAUCUUCCACAGUACCUUAUAUACUACUUUCAACAAAAAUUAGUUAAUGUUUGUUUGCAUUUGAGUUGGAAUGUCAUGUGCUUGAUAGAAUGAACCUUAGUCUUAGUUCCUUAGUCUAACCUCUGGUUUCUUAGUCUUAGUUCCUUAGUCUAACCUCUGGUUUGAGUCUCAGGAAUAUAUUUACAUCCAGGUUUGGUCCUUUGAAGAUAUCACAGACUAGUCCCUUUUUCACAUGAUGUCCUUUAAAUAUUUGAGUAAUAUCUGAUAUUUUAACAUUUACUAUGUGAUACAUCCUGUGCUAAGCAUUUUGUAACUAAAAUAAUGAAGAUUUUUGUUAUGCAUUAUAAAUUGUUCUUAGUAGCCUUCAAAUACACCACAAUCUGUGCAGUUAGUUAAAUUCAACAGCAGUUCAUUUUUGCAGAAUCUGUGAAGUGGGGCAAAACGUCCUUCAAUUAUCAGUAAGUUACCUACUUAGCUCUUGCAGGCAGGUAAUGCAUUGCACUCCAUUUCCAAUCAAUAAUAUGUGAUGAGCAUCCAGAGAAUUAUAUAAAAAUGAUUAUGAAGAAAUUAUCUUGAUUUGAUUUGAGGACAUUAAAUAUGAAAACACAAAAGCAUAAAAAUGAUACAAAUAUACUGGCUUCUGCAAAAAUCUGAAUGAGGAAGUUCUUAGUAAUAUGUUUCCUGUGGCAGAGGGAAGUAAUUUUUUUUUUAAUAAGGUCUUCUCUCCCUGAAGACCUGAUUAUAAUUUUUAAAAGAUAACUCUUAAUGCUAUAUUAAGUAUAGUGAGUGCUUUUAGGUAAAGUUGCCUUAAAUUGGGUUUUAGUAGAAAGAUCUUCUACCUGUACUUUGUCCCUGAUCCUGUGUUUUCCUUCACAGUUGUUAAAAUAAUUAUCCCCCUCCCAAAUUUUGCUAAGGCCUAAAACAGAACAGUAGUGUAUACAAUAAUGAAUAUGCCAGGCUAAUGUUGGUAUUCAUUGUGGCUAGAUUAUUUUAUUUUAAUGUUAUUAUUUUUUUUUGAGUUUUAAAAUAAAUGCAACAAGGUCAGUAAUCACACUGUCAAGGCUAAAGCCAGAUCAGUCAGUGAAUAAAAUAGUUAAAAUCUAUUAUAGGGUUAUAGUUGAUUAUUAGCUUUAUUGUGUUGUAAGACUAGAUAAAAAAAAGACUAGAAGACUAGCUUCAUGUUAUAAAAAUUAUAAACAAUAUACUUCAAAUAUUAAUAUGAAUUGCUGUCUCAAAGGCUAAUUCAUUGAUCAAGAAAUGCAAUAUAUUAGUCACAGAGUUUCAGAAUAUAUUAUGGUGACUUUAAAAAACCAUUUUUAUUGUCUGUGAUUUCAAAUUUAACUUCUUUGUAAACAUCUGUGAUGUACUAUAUAGUUAAAAUUAACAGACUGAAAUUAUUACUUUUUUGGGUGUAAAAAUAGCACAUUUUAAACACCAGAACUACAUCAAAAAUGAUGAAAUUGAAGAAAUAAAAAAAAUUUGUAUCUUCUUAUUUCGUGUGGUCAAAGCUUUAUUGUGGCACAGUGAUGCAAAAUGACCUAUAAUGGCAUAUGGGGGUGCUAGAUACUAAAAAUUACAUUUUAAGAUAUAUGUCUGCUUACUGCCAAAACUUAUUUACUUUAUAGCUCAGGAAACACACCUGUAAGUUGUUUUUUUAAAAAAAAAUUUUGGAGGGUAUUUUUUGAGAAAGGAUCUUGCUCUGUUGCUCAGGCUGGAGUGCAGUGGCAUGAUUGUAGCUCACUGCAACCUCAGUCUCCUGGGCUCAGGUGAUACUCCCUCCUUAGCCUCCCGAGUAACUGAGGCUAUGAAUGUGUGCCACCGUGUCCAGCUAGUUUUUAUGAUAAUCAGUUUAAACUUUCUAUGUACUUUAAGUGUGGGAGUCAAAUGCUGUUAGUUUUCAUUUUUUAUUAUAGCAUUUUGACUAUAACUGAUUGCAACUUAUAAAAUGAUUAAUAUUUUAGUCUAAUAUAUUAGAGAGGACUUCACAUUUCCAAGGUUGCAUUUUUCUUUCACGGAGGGGAAAGAUGUUCAUUGUAGCUGUGGACUUUCUUAGCAGUCAUUUCUGGAUUCCUUCUCAAUGUAACAUUUCACCCUGUGAGUCUUUCAGAAAUGAAUAAACCACAGCUCUGCCCUUGAGGAGCUUAUAGACCUCUGAGAAAAAUAGAUCAAUAAGUUAUUAACCCAAAUGGUAAUGGUUGUGGCAGCAGAGAGAGUAGCACCUGCCUAGCUUUAGGUCGUGGUUAAGGACAACUUGAAGAAUAAUGCUGGGCUGAGGCUGGGAGGUAAGUUAGCUGAAGACAGGGACAACAUGAGCAGAAGCCUGGCCUAUUCUUCAUACAUGUUAGUUUGCCACUGCCUUUUUUUGUAGUGUGGCAGACAACAUUGCCUAUUUGCUCAGUAUCCAAGCUAUCAGAUUAUUAAGCAAAAGUACUAAAUGCAGAGCUUUGUGGCAGUGACUGGAAAUCUUCCUCUAGGUUACUGUUCCCCAAACUUGAGAACUCUGACCAUUAAAGUGUUGUCACACCCUACAUCAAAAAAUUGCUGCAUGAAAAGUUAAAUAUUAUUAUUUUAGGUGAUUAUUUGGUGCUAAUAUGAUUUUAGACACGGAAGUGAACAUGGGCAGCAAAGUCGGUAUAGUAUUACAUGGUUAUAAGGUGGUCAUACAUAUACUCAUAUACAAAAUGAAAUGGUUUUUAGCAAGAGCUUUUUUUAGGAACCAUAACGUGUGUGCCAAUCAGUUACCAGCUAUCUGUUAAUUUUUUGGCAUUGAGUUUAUUCAUUUACAAUUUACAACUUCUUUUGUCUCUUCACUUACUGGAAAUUGAAUUAUCGUUUAUUAUUUUAGAAAAAAAACCAAAAAGUUAAAAAGUGAGAGUAUAAAAAGAUGAAUGAGAAGAGCCCUUCCCUUAUGAAACUACCCGGAAACAAGUUAAAGAACAGAUAUAGAUGUGAUGAACUGUGAAAGCCUUGCAAAUUCCCAUCCUUUUAGAACUUCCUGUUCAUCAUGAUUUUGCAAGCAUUGAUAGUAAUUCUGCAGCUAUAAUCUUAAAAUUGUCUUCUGACAAUGGAAAAUAAAAUCUGACAACUAUAAUUUUUUGAAUUUUAGUCUUUCUAGUUUGGGAACUUCUUGAAGACAUACAUGUUGCAUUCCUGGCACUUUGCGUGUAGUUAAGUACCUUAUAAACCUAAUUGAUUGGUUGACUAGUCAUGAAAUACUUAAAAUGUUCUUUGAAUGUCUCUCCUGGAAGAAUGCUUCAAAUGUGGAACUUCUGUUACUGUGUGUAUUAUAAGAAUAAGAUAGUUGCCCAAUUCUUGAUCCUGUUAGAAGAAAUCUCUGCUUUUCUUAUACGUUCGACAUUAAAUGCUAAAUGAAGGGUGGGGUUUCUGCAGACAUUAUACAAUUUUUUUCUUCAGACAUUUAUCAUCAGAUUUUCCUUUUGUUGUUAUUCUGAUCAAUUAUUUUAUCCUACAGCAUUUACUAGAAAUUAUAAAAUGUAAUCUUAAAUUCUGUAUUUUAGAUAGCAGACUUUUAUCUUGCCAAAAGCUGAUUAAAGUAGCAAUAAAUUAGUAAAUCCUCAUAAAGGAAAUUUCUUAUUACCUAAAUAAUAAGUUAUAAUCUUGUUGUAAACUAUGUUAUCAGUUUCUCCUUUUUCCAUGUCAGAUGUGGUCUAUAGAACAAUGAUUUUCAGUCUGGAUAUUCUGAAACUGCCACUGUUGUGAUUUAUUUUGGUCACAAUAUUUAGUCCAUCUUGAAAUUUUAAAUUACAUUAUUGUAAAAUCAUGUUUUCCUUUUUACUUGCAUUUAAAAUAUUCUUAAUUUCUUUUUCUGAUGUUUCCUCAUUACUGGAGCGUUUUUUUAAAGUCCAUGUAUCUUAUCUCUAUAAUUGGUACCUUUGUAAAAAGUACAGUAUUUGAAAAAUUAUUCUUUGCAUUUUCUAACACAAUCCUUUUGUAAUUUUCUUUCUGUUUAUUCAGAGGUCUUCUCUUUCUGCUCUUAUUGUGCUGAUCAUCCCUUAAAUGUUUUCUUACCUCAGGAUUCUCUAAGUCUCCUAUUUGCCUUCAGUGAUCUCAGCAGAUUUGCUUUUGCUAUCACUUAAAUGCUUUUGGUUUUUAAAUUUGUUUCUAGUUUAGAUCAAUUGUCUGCUACAGGAUAUCCCACCUUCAAGUUUACCUCAAAUUUAAUAUGUGCAAAACAGAAUUCAUUCUCUCUUCUUGAUAUCCUCCUUUUACCCCAGAGUGUAUCCUCUUGUGUUCCUUGUUGGUCAGUGACACUAGCAUCCAACCAGUUGUCCAAACUUUCCUGUCUCUUCCUCUUUACCUUCUAUACUCAGUUGUUUCCAAGUCAGCUUCCUGCAAGUUUGCCUAGGCAUUUUUCUCAUGUUGCAGAACUUUAUGCUUACUUUCAAAUUAAAACCACAUUGUUUAAACCUCUUAAGAGCCUUAAUAGAUGUGGCUCCCUUUGCCUGGGAAUAAUAAUCCUCUCCUCUUUGCCUAAUUUCUACUUUUUCUUCAAGACUUAAUUUAGUCAUUACUUCUUGCAGAAAGGUUUGUUAUCCCAUUAGCUAUUAUCUCAUAGCAACCUGUGAUAGUUGUUAUCACAGAGAUAAUUCUUUCUGUAUGUGAUUAUCUUUUCCCACCAGACUACGAGCUACUAAAUGGCCAGGGAUUGUGGCCUGUAUUUGUAUUCCCUACAUUUAGUUUAGUGCCUAGGGCAUGGUAGGCUUCACUAAAUGAUUGUUAAAAGAAUACAUGAGAUUGGGUAUUGUUUUUCCCAUUUAUGUAUAUUUCUGAGGCACAUUUGUUUUUUGGUUUUCAGAGGGUAGCAGUUUCACCUGUGUCCCUCUCUGAGUUGAGAACCAACUGAAAUACAGAAAUAUAAGAGUCAGUUUGAAGCAAGUCAAAAUACCAGUUUUACUACUAGUAAAGCUGGGUUGGAGAAUGCAUCUUGAUCUUUGUCCAUUAUCAGUCUUUCUGUUACUUUUCCUCCAAAUCUAAACUUUCCAAUGAUGUAUCUGAGGGACACCCCAAGUUAGCAGAGCAAACACAUUGACCAAGCCUUUUGCAAGGAAGGCACAUUGAUUCAAACUGCCCUAUAACUCCAUGGAGAUCAUGUAAAGAUACACACUUCCAGACCCAGGUAUGCUUAUAAGCAGGAAGAAUGAAUUGCAGACUGCACAUCUGAAGGAGAAACUCUUAAGAGUUUGUUUAUUCAUUCAUUUAACAAAUAGAUAUUGAGCUCUUACCAUGUGCUGGAUGGACAUUGUGCAGAUGGUGCAGAUAUAGAUUUGGUGCUUAUGUUUUAGAGCCUACUAGGUUCCUUUUUUCCAGACUGACGAGUAAAAUAAGUCACUUUUCCUCUUAUAGCAGAAGUCUUCUCUAGGGAAGAUAGGAACAGAUGAAUAGAAUAGUUUAUCCAAAGGUAUAACCUGUUCUCUAGCCAUUGCAUGUAAAAUAAUUCCCAAGGACUGAUAAUUUUAAGAACACGGUGGAAUGAAAUACAGAGAAACAUAUCAGCACAAUCUUAAGAGAAAUUUCAAAGGUCUGGUCAUGUUUUAGAAAAACGUGGAAAAUUUGAUCAUGAUAAUUUCACUUUUCCUUUACUAUACUUGAAAUACUUGGCUUAGGAUUUUAAAGACCAUUUAGUCAUGAUUUAUUUCUGACAUGAGUCUGCUAAGUAUUCAUUUAUACAAGUUACUUAGAAAAUCUACUCCCUAAUGAGGUCUGGUGGCAGCAUUUGAAAAUAAUGGGGAAAUUCUAGUGGUCUUAGCCACAAAUACCAGCUCCCUGUUGCCAGUGAUAGGUCUUUAUCACAUCAGCAUCUCCUGUGAAGUCUUUUCUGAAUGUCAUAGCAUUCAUUAUUUUUCUCACUCAUUUGGUCUCCUGGUUCUUUAUAGUGCUAUUUAUGAUUCAGUUAUUGUAAUAUAUAAGAUGAUCUUACGAGGUGCAGCCUAUAUUAUAACUUAUCUAUUGCAUAACUUAGGUAAGGACAGUUUCCCGAAUACCUGAAGUACACAAUAAGAAAAAGUCAUAUGCUAAAUUCUCUACAUCAUUAUACAAGGGGAGUGGUUCUCUAGAGCAAUGGCUCCCGAAUGAACGUGGGUGUGCAUGAGGGCCAUGGUGGGAGGGGGAGGCUUAUUUUUAGAAAGAAGAAUUCUGGUAUGCCAUCCCAGGGAUUGAUUCAGAAAGUCCUGGGUUGGGGGCAGGGAGUAUUCACUUUUAAAAGUAAUCUAGGAGAUUCUUCUUCAGAGGGCUCAUAGGCCACCCUUAGAGAAGCAUUGUACUAUGGAAACAUAGUUCGCUUUGAUUGUAUUUAUUCCAAGGCAACCUUGUACAAUUAAAGAAUAAAUACAAACAGUAAGAGAAGAUUUUUAUGAAUGUUGAUUUUGUUAGGGAGUUAGAAGUUGUGGUAAUUGUUUCUUAGAGAUGUGUUAAUGUUAAACGUUUGAUAGAUAAAUCAGUAUAAUUAGGUAUAUAUAGUUAUACCCCAAGACUGAGGGUAAAUCCAGUCAUUUUCUAUUGUUACUAUUUUGUUUGCAUCUAGCUUUGUUUUUAGUAAAAGAACUAUAUAUUUUGUUUUCUGUAAUGUUGAUUUCUUACAAUCUCAAUAUAUAUUAGACUGCUUAAUAUCAGGAACCAGUUGUAUGAAUAUUUGCAAAUUUCACAAUGCCUUAUAUGUAGUAGACAUUUUAUAAAACAUUUUCAUUACAAAUGUUGAGUAAAUGAGCUUUCUAUAAAAAUUGUUGCAUUAUUUGAUACAUGGUAAGUAUUAUAGUUAUUAUAUAUGAAAAAAAACCAGCUAACAUCUUAGGGUUUUUCAUUUGUUUUACUGGUCUUCUAUGUUUCUUUUUGUCUUCAUCUUUUUCUGCCCUGACUGGAUUCUUGCUGCUUUUCUUCAUUUUGCAGUUGUAGCUGAAAAUUUGACUAUUUGAUACCUUUAGACAUGUUCCAAUACGCAGGAGAAUAAGUAGGAUUAUCCUGGCUCCUGGUUUGCCUAGGAUGGUCAAAGUUUAUGCCACUGGUCCUGGCAUAAUUAAUGAUAGCACCCCCCAGCCACUCUCAAAAUGCCAAAUUAUAUAAAUUCCUUUGAAGCUUGAAACCAUGUAAAUAAGUGAUUUGCAAGUUGAGUUCUUGCCUUCACAUAUUCUUGCCACAAUCCCAUUUUUUGUUGUACUAAUGUUAUUGGUUCUUUCUGUAUUUUGAUUUCUAAUUGUGAGCAUUUUUGAGACCCCCUAAUUUGAGGUGUCUUUAUUUUUUAUGAGAAUUUUUCUGUUUUGUAUGUGGAAUUUUUAAUUUACCUUAAUAGUAUUUUUAAACUACAGAAGAUUUUAGUUGUCUCAAAAUAAUUUGUUCUUUUAAAAUGGUUUAGAAAUGAGUGACAGACAGUUCCUGGGCCAUUAGCUUAUGUUCAAGCAUUGAUAUAACAAAAGCAGUUUUCAAAAAGACAUUUAACAAUGUUCCUUGGUGUUCCAUGAAUAUUUAUUCAGGUUGUUAGAAGUCCUUUACAGGAAAUAUUUAGCUUAUAAAUAGGCUAAUAAAGGGGAAGCUGUAAGUUCAGUUUCUUUUGUCCUCUUGGCAUUAAAGGAAGCUGUUACCAGAAACACAGAUCUCAGUUUUUAAGGUAAAAUACUCCUAUACAUGUUAGCUAGCUUUGUUACUUUGUGUAUUUACCAAGAUUUUCUCUAAGACAUGGAAGUAAGUUCCUAUAGAAAGCUCCAAAGAUAUUGAUUGAUUGGUUGAAAUACACUCUAUAAAUGGAAACUGUCUCCAUAAUGACUUUACCAAUUGUUUCCCUACAAAUAUAGGGAAACACUUUAUUUUUGCCAACAAGUGCUUUUGUUAGACUGCAUUUUAGCAGGACUCUUAGAACAUGUUAGUGCUUAGUACUAUUAUAAAUUCACUCUCAGUUCCAUUAUAAAUUGUGGAUAGUCUGAUUUGCCUUAUGCCUUUCCUCUGUUUUUCUCCCUCUUAAUCACGAUCCCUAACAUUUGUCUUAGACCACUACAUAAUUACUACACUCCUCUAAAACAUAUUAAUUAGCAAAGUAAAUUUCAAUGUGAUAGUACCAUGGUUUGCAUUAAAGAAGAAAGUCACUGCUUACAUCUUUUUAAAAAAACAGUUACAACAAUGAAAAUGUUCUUUUUUUAAUUCUAAGAGUACUACUGAUAUUGUAGAAGACAUUAGCCAAUCUUUUAUAUAUUAAAAAAGGGAAUCACAUACUGUUUCAGUUUUUAUUUUUGCAUCAUUUGAUUACUUACCUCUGUAGAUUGGGACACCGGGGCGGUAUAGUCUUCUUGCCAAGACUCUUCCCCCUGAGCACAUUGAAGAUGGUCAGUGACAUGUAGGGUCCAGGGACAUGGUCUUGAAAAUAGGAAUGAACCAUGCAGUGUUGUACAGUGGUGGGGCAGAGGUAUGAGUACUUUUCUCUCCUGGUUGCAGCUUUGGUUUCUCUUUCAUCCGUUGGGUUGUUUCCUAUUUUGCAAACUAAGCCAGGAUCAGAUGAAAUGAAAAGGGAAUGAUAUCUGAUUUUAAUAUUUGUGUUAAUUUUUUUUCAAAUGAUGAUUCUAGAAGCUUUUCGAAUGAAAUCUCUCAGAAUAAUAUUUUCCAAAAGCUGGGAUUAUUCUGUAUUUUAUUGCUCUUGUCUUUGUGUAACUCUGCUGAGUAAUAUUUAAUUUUUUUCCAAUAAAUAUGAUAAUAUACAGUAAAGUUAAAUUGAAGUGUAAGUCUACAACAUGAUUACUAAUAAGUAGGAUAAUGUCUAAAAUUAAAACUUUUUAAAUUAAAAAUUGUAAUAGUGGGAAAAAAUCAGAUAUAAAGUAUAAACCAGUUAGUUGCCUCAGGAAAAAAAGGUGCUGUUUUUUUUUUUCUACAGUUUCCCAGAAUUGUUUGGAGAAGUGUACAAGAGUUUUGUCUGUGUUAUGCCUAUUAUAGAGCAAAGUAUUGCAAUGUAAGGAGAAGACCAUCUUUUAAAACAGAAUUGGAGCUUUAAUUCUAUUUAUUGCUUUGUUGUCCUCUUUUCCAUAAGGUUUAUGUGCCUAGGAAUUAAAAACAAGUAGUGAAAUUGAGAAUGAAAGGAGAGAAGGUAUACGAUUAUAUGUGGAAAGAAUCAUGUAAUAAAAUACUCCUCUAAUGGAUUAAAAUCCUUUUAAAAGGAACACUUUUCUGAAGAUAAGAUUAUUUUGUUCCUUUCUUUUGACCCCAUAUCUAAUUAGUCACCAAACUCUUUUCAUGUUUUCCCACUUUUCUUUCAAAGCUCUGGGACACUAGAAUAUGCAUUUUGUUUUUCCCAUGUGCCGUCCUGCCUAGUGUUGCUUGCGUUGUUCCAUUUGAUUACAGUUGUCCUUCACUGUCUCUAGUUUAUUCCUGUAGUUCAGUCUUACUUGUUCUUCACGGGAGUCCUCAGUAUCCAGUUCGAGUUCCAUGUCCUUGGUAAAACCUCUUUUCACUUUAGCCGCAAGUUGUUUUCUCUCUCCUCUGAACCUCUGUGGUGCUUACAGCUGUGCAGUCUAUUUGACAUUGGAGAGCCUUUGUCCUAAAAUGUCCAAGGUUUGUUUUAAAACUUAAUUUUUAAACUUUGUCUUUUAAAGUAUGUAGUCACCUUUUUAAGUCCUUGUAGUUGUCAUUUGAAGCAUAGUUUGCUAAAAUAACACCUAUAUUACAGGCUUUAUAGAUAAUACAUAUGUGUAUGUGUGUAUAUAUAUAUAAAAAUACAGAAUUAUAUAUAAUACGUGUGUGUGUGUGUAUAUUGCUCUUUGGGUAGCUCUGUUGAGUAAUUAAUUUUUUUCUGAUAAGUAUGAUAAUAUGCAGUACACAGACAUAUUUAGCUUUACUGCUGUGUAUUACAUAUAUGUGUAUAUACACACACAUACACACAUAUUAUAUGUAAAUUGUUUUGGUACCUGGAAAGGAUAUGUGUGAGUGGAACUGUAAUAUUGCUAAAUAUUUUUGAUUGUAUGAAGUAAAUGUCUUGUUCUGACAUCAACUGAAUGAGUAACUGGACUUUUAAUUUUAACCUUGGAGGGAAUAUAUGUGAGGCAGACUCUUUUAAAGGGUUUUGGACACCACAGAGCUAGAGUUCUUGAAGUGGUUAAUUUUAAAAAUCUUCUAAUAGAAAGUCUGUCUCUUUUCACCUUGAUUACUGGUGGACUCUGCUAGACCUAAAAAUAAAGCAUGAAUUGUUCAAAGUGAUUCAUUUGACAUUGUCAUCUGUUUGUUGGAAAAAUCAUAUCAUUCUGGCACUUAUUUAGUGUUUUAUGGUGGACAGUGUACUUUAUUGAUUUUUAUAGCGUAUAGGAGCAGAUGUUAAACUCACUUUAUAUUUUGUUUCCUUAUUUAUUUAGGAAAAAGCAUUUUUAUAAAUGUCUGCUUUAUGCCUGACAUGCAUAACAAUGAGUAAGAUACAUGGGCUUUGCAUUUGAGGAAUUCAUAUUCUGGUGGUGAAGACAGACACAUAUAUGUAAACGAGCAGUAGAUUGUUACAGGUGCUGUGAUAGAAAUAUAUAAUGAGGGCAUGAAGGACCAAAAUCCAGUAAUCGUAGGCACUGUCAUUUAAAAGUAUGAAAUCUAGUGAGCCAUACAUAUGUCAGUCAAUUUCUAUUAUGUUACAUGUGAGAAUUAAAUGAGAGAAUUGCUACAUAGAAGGUGUAGAUACUAUUAUUGUAUGCUUUUAUAGAUUAUGAAACAAACUUAAUUCAAAGCCAUACAGUCAGUUUCCAUAAUAUGAAUACAAUCUAAACAUUCUUCAUCUCCAGUGACAGUGUUACUAACUUAGUAUUUUUGUUUUGGAGGAUAGCUUUAUCCCAAGUAGCCAGUGGCAUGGUGGCAGUUAGUGGUGGAGACAUCAAUAUUUCCAGUUAAAUUAUCAUUGAAUAGUAUAGUCCCUUGAAAGUGGAAGUUGCUUAUUUUUAAAGGGGUCUUUUUUUUUUUAAUGAUCCAAGUCCCCAAAUUUAUAGAGUUGCAUAGGAAAGCAAAUGUUAUCUCAAACCAGAAGUACUCAGUGGUCAACCAACCACUUACAAUAUUGGUUCCCAGUAUUCAGAAUUCUCCUAGUACCUUUGAGUGCCUGCGUGCCUAAUCCAUACUAUCAGUUUCACCUUGAGUUUCUCUAUGCAGCUGCUCAAGUCCUUCUAUGAAUGCCUCUUUGAGACAGGAUGGAUUGGAAAUUAGCUCUAAUACCUCAUUAUUGAAGGAGGAGGAUGUUUCCUCUUCUAGAGGUCAAUUGGCAUCACUACUGUUUAGGGACUAAGAGGCAUUGCUGAAUCUAUAUGAGAAUGAUGUUAGGGGAGCAAAGGAGAAGAAUUUUCUUGCAGUGUUGAGUAGAUAAAACAAACUGCUUGCUUCUUCUACUAUACUGUCACAAUACUUGAACACUUCUGUGAACAAAUGUGUGGGAGAUUUUCCCCAAGCACCGAGCUAGCAAUUCCCCAGCUGGGUGUCCUCUGACGUAAUUCAGUUCUUAGCAAUAUUUACAUGGAGGUAGUGUCACAACCCACAGGUUGAGGGCUCUGUCCCACAGGACUGCCUCCCUCCGCCCCCCUCCCCUCCAGCACACACACACACUCACAUACACACACACAUGCUCUCUCUGUCUCUCUGUCUCUGUCUCUCUCUCAAGAUGCCAGUUGGAAGCCCCAGGUUGUUUUACCUGUGCUUCUGCCAGCUAUAAAUCAGGAUUCCCACACUCCCUCCUUGGGCUCAGCUAAUUUGCUAGAGUGGCUCACAGAACUUAGGGAAAUACUUUACUUACAUUUACCAGUUUAUUAUAAAGGCUAUUAAGAAGGAGACAGAUGAACAGCCGGAUGGAAAAGAUGCAUAGGUCCAAGUAUGGGAGAAGGAGUGAGGAGCUUCCAUAUAUAUUUGCUCCAGGAGUAUGCUGCUGCUGUUCCGCUUUGCGUCCUCGCUACAAACGCCUGGUGGACAACAUAUUCCCUGAAGAUCCAAAAGAUGGCCUUGUGAAAACUGAUAUGGAGAAAUUGACAUUUUAUGCAGUAUCUGCUCCAGAGAAACUGGAUCGAAUUGGUUCUUACCUGGCAGAAAGGUUGAGCAGGGAUGUUGUCAGACAUCGUUCUGGGUAUGUUUUGAUUGCUAUGGAGGCACUGGACCAACUUCUCAUGGCUUGCCAUUCUCAAAGCAUUAAGCCAUUUGUAGAAAGCUUUCUUCAUAUGGUGGCAAAGCUGCUGGAAUCGGGGGAACCAAAGCUUCAAGUUCUUGGAACAAAUUCUUUUGUCAAAUUUGCAAAUAUUGAAGAAGACACACCAUCCUAUCACAGACGUUAUGACUUUUUUGUGUCUCGAUUCAGUGCCAUGUGCCAUUCCUGUCAUAGUGAUCCAGAAAUACGAACAGAGAUACGAAUUGCUGGAAUUAGAGGUAUUCAAGGUGUGGUUCGCAAAACAGUCAACGAUGAACUUCGGGCCACCAUUUGGGAACCUCAGCAUAUGGAUAAGAUUGUUCCAUCCCUCCUGUUUAACAUGCAAAAGAUAGAAGAAGUUGACAGUCGCAUAGGCCCUCCUUCUUCUCCUUCUGCAACUGACAAAGAAGAGAAUCCUGCUGUGCUGGCUGAAAACUGUUUCAGAGAACUGCUGGGUCGAGCAACUUUUGGGAAUAUGAAUAAUGCUGUUAGACCAGUUUUUGCGCAUUUAGAUCAUCACAAACUGUGGGAUCCCAAUGAAUUUGCAGUUCACUGCUUUAAAAUUAUAAUGUAUUCCAUUCAGGCUCAGUAUUCUCACCAUGUGAUCCAGGAGAUUCUAGGACACCUUGAUGCUCGUAAAAAAGAUGCUCCCCGGGUUCGAGCAGGUAUUAUUCAGGUUCUGUUAGAGGCUGUUGCCAUUGCUGCUAAAGGUUCCAUAGGUCCGACAGUGCUGGAAGUCUUCAAUACCCUUUUGAAACAUCUGCGUCUCAGCGUUGAAUUCGAAGCAAAUGAUUUACAGGGGGGAUCUGUAGGCAGUGUCAACUUAAAUACAAGUUCCAAAGACAAUGAUGAGAAGAUUGUGCAGAAUGCUAUCAUCCAAACAAUAGGAUUUUUUGGAAGUAACCUACCAGAUUAUCAGAGGUCAGAAAUCAUGAUGUUCAUUAUGGGGAAAGUACCUGUCUUUGGAACAUCUACCCAUACUUUGGAUAUCAGUCAACUAGGGGAUUUGGGAACCAGGAGAAUUCAGAUAAUGUUGCUGAGAUCUUUGCUUAUGGUGACCUCUGGAUAUAAAGCGAAGACGAUUGUUACUGCACUGCCAGGGUCUUUCCUGGAUCCUUUGUUAUCACCAUCUCUCAUGGAGGACUACGAACUGAGACAGUUGGUCUUGGAAGUAAUGCAUAAUCUCAUGGAUCGUCAUGACAAUAGGGCAAAGCUUCGAGGGAUCAGAAUAAUACCGGAUGUAGCUGACCUAAAGAUAAAAAGAGAAAAAAUUUGCAGACAAGACACAAGUUUCAUGAAAAAGAAUGGGCAACAGCUGUAUCGGCACAUAUAUUUGGGUUGUAAAGAGGAAGACAACGUUCAGAAAAACUAUGAACUACUUUAUACUUCUCUUGCUCUUAUAACUAUUGAACUGGCUAAUGAAGAAGUAGUUAUUGAUCUCAUUCGACUGGCCAUUGCUUUACAGGACAGUGCAAUUAUCAAUGAGGAUAAUUUGCCAAUGUUCCAUCGUUGUGGAAUCAUGGCACUGGUUGCAGCAUACCUCAACUUUGUAAGUCAGAUGAUAGCUGUCCCUGCAUUUUGCCAGCAUGUUAGCAAGGUUAUUGAAAUUCGAACUAUGGAAGCCCCUUAUUUUCUACCAGAGCAUAUCUUCAGAGAUAAGUGCAUGCUUCCAAAAUCUUUAGAGAAGCAUGAAAAAGAUUUGUACUUUCUGACCAACAAGAUUGCAGAGUCGCUAGGUGGAAGUGGAUAUAGUGUUGAGAGAUUGUCAGUUCCGUAUGUACCACAAGUAACAGAUGAAGAUCGACUUUCUAGAAGAAAAAGCAUUGUGGACACCGUAUCCAUUCAGGUGGAUAUUUUAUCCAACAAUGUUCCUUCUGAUGAUGUGGUUAGUAACACUGAAGAAAUCACUUUUGAAGCAUUGAAGAAAGCAAUUGAUACCAGUGGAAUGGAAGAACAGGAAAAGGAAAAGAGGCGUCUUGUGAUAGAGAAAUUUCAGAAAGCACCUUUUGAAGAAAUAGCAGCACAGUGUGAAUCCAAAGCAAAUUUGCUUCAUGAUAGACUUGCCCAAAUAUUGGAACUCACCAUACGUCCUCCUCCCAGUCCAUCAGGAACACUGACCAUUACUUCUGGGCAUGCCCAAUACCAAUCUGUCCCAGUCUAUGAGAUGAAGUUUCCAGAUCUGUGUGUGUACUGAUCGGCGCAUGAAGACCUCAGGAUAUGAUUUGUAAAGCCUAAAAAUUAAGGCCAAGCUGAGCUUUCAGGGUUUACUUAAUGUGUAUUAACAUACUUCUUGAAAAUAAUGAUGGAACAUAUCUUUAACCAAAUGUUUGGCAUACCAUAUUAGAAGUUUUGGAGCUAUAUAUAAUUUCGAGUACUUUCAAAGAUAGAUUUAUGCCAUGUUAAUUUGCUUUGAGGUUCCUGUUGCCUUUUUAAGUUGAACAUGUUUUGGUUUCACUUUAUUCCACUGUUAAGUAGUAUGUUUUAAACUUUUCACAAAUGUAAUGUUUUUUAAAAAGUAAGCCUUCAGAGGAUUGAAACUGUAUAAAUUGUUUAUCUCUUAAACAUCUACACAGCCGCUUAGAUGUAGAAUUUUUGUUGUUGUUUUCUGCAAAGGCAGAUACAUUUAAAUAUAUUCCUAGUCCUGGGACUGCAAAACUGUUCGGUGGCUUUUUGUCCCCAUGCUUUAGAUAAGCUGGGAUAGGCACCUUGCUAUUCAGUUACUAUAAUAAUAUGUGAUAGGCAUUCCUCAUCUUCUUCACAAUAAUAGGACAUCUGUUGAAUAGCAUUCCUCGAAUAUAACCCUAAAAACGCCAUACUUUAAAUUGUCUGGUUCUUGUAAUAUUGUGUUUCCUGCCAAGAGUUUGACCAUUCUGCUUGAGAAGUGUAGAGCUUACUCUUGGAGUACCAAACUGUGCAAUAUUUUUACAUCAUAAGAUGUAUUAGUUUACAGGCUGUGCUUUGAAAUUAUAGUAGUAUUUUGCUGUGGCUCCAUUAAUUAAAUGAGAUAUAUAUUUAGUGCAGAAAAAAGACAUUUAAAACAGCUAUUAGUUCACCUGUGAAGAGUCUGUACAUUUUGAUUUCUAUUAAGAGCACAUUUAUUUACAUUUGUAUAUUAUUUUAAAUCCUCAUAGUCAAAAAAUUCUCCAGAUGGACUUUUAAUUUGUAAGAUUUGAACUGUGACUUGUAUACAUCUGUUUAGAAUCAAUUAUAUUUGAAAAGCUGCCUGUGUUUUAACAGUCAAGUGUGCUAAAGUUUGUCAAUUUAAGCUGCUUUUGAUUUCAGCUACCAAGAUCACAGGUGCACUCUACACAUAACACUGACAGACCCAUAACAUUACAUACAUCUUAGUGAAUUCUAUCACAUGGUAAAAUGAACAGCUUUCUUUGUAACUCAUAAAAUUCUCUUAGGACAUUUUUAUAAAGUCACCUGUUUAUAGUUCUAUCUUUUCAGAUUCCAUUUCUUUUUACAUAAAACAGCAUACAUAUCAAAAACUGUAGCCUAGAAUACAGUUUAAUUUUUGGCUUUUGUUUUUGUUUAAAAAAUUGCAGUGAAGAAUGGGAUGUUUGUGUUUAUGGCUAUUUGGGCACCUUUAGUAGAAACAGACAAAAGUAAGGAAACGAUAAUAGGACAAGCAUACUUGAAAAUUUCUGAAUACUUAAACAAAAGCGCAACAUCUUGAAAACCAGUCUAGUCAUUGAAACCUAUGAAAUGACACUGAAAGAUCCUGGGCUGCUUCUUAAAUAAGUAGAUCAGCAAGACUUGUUUCAGAGUGACAGUGGAGUCGUUACCGCUGGAGGACUAAAGGGCCCUGUGGCAGCUGUCACUGGAACUUUGCCUCUUGAUCAGGAAAAAUGCUUCACCAGUCCGUAAAGCCAAGUUGUAUUUUUUUAAUUGCCCUUUUUUCCUUCUGUAUUUUUAAAGAAGGAUGUUAAUUUUUGACUAUAUAUUUUAAAAAAAUCUAAGCAGGGGGACAUGCAAAAACAAUCAUCAUCCACUUGGAUGUCAUUUUAUAGAUUAACACUGUGUGCUUUUGUAUGGAAAAAAUAUAUAUAAUUUAAUAGUAUAAAAAAUAAAAUAUAUAUUCAUUUGCACUUACGUGAAACACAAACUUUGCUCUACAAAAUUUCGUGUUUCUUAGUGAUUUUAAAAUGCAUGUAUUGCAUGUAAAGGAAAACCAUUACAAUUAAUGUUUAUCACACCUUUAUCUUGGUCUUUGUUGAUUUGGGUUUUGUUGGGGUUUUUGUUACUGUUUUUAAAUUACAGUAGGCUUCUAUAUAUCCUGGAUUUCUGAACUGGUCUUGUUGACAAGGAUUCCCAAGAAAUGGAUCUUUUCACUGGCUGACUCUCCCAUAUCUGCAAGAGAUUCUGCAGGAACUGGGUGUGCACACGGUGUUGUAGCCAGUUCAGGUACUGAAUAUUUAGGAUUUGGUGAAGUUCACUGUAUUGCUAUAUUUUUGUAGAUAAAUAAAACUCAAUAAAUUGUUAAUCAUUCUCUUUUUGCUGUAUAGAAUUGCUUAUAUCACUCUUUCUUUCAUGACAUUGGUUAACAUUUAAAUGUUCCUCCUGUACUUGUGUUGUCUGUGACCGCUUAUAGAGUUUUAUUGUUAUUGGUGUUUACCUGAAUACCUAUGCGUACACACACACAUAUUUCCUUAAUACUUCUGAACUCAUUAUCUUUUAGAAUAAUAAUACUACUACACUUUACCAGCAAUUAACUUCUCCCUACCCAAAAUGUUUUUCUUCCUGUCUGAAAAUGGAACUAAUUUGUCUUAUUCGUGCUUAUAUCUGUAUUAAAUGCAAUAAAGUUAGUUUUUGAAAUGUAAAAAUUCACUGUGCAAUUCAUAUGUCAGCAAUAAAACAUAGAUUAUUUGUAUAUAAGUUCAUUUUUAUAGCUAUUGUUACAUUUAAUUAAAUUUAUUCAAUAUUUGCUUAAAUUAAAAA